GGGCAGAGCAACAUUGUUUUGACAGUGAAAAUUACCAAUUUAUAAUUUUUUAAGAAAAGCAUGCCUAGCACAGACCACCUGAUUACCAAGAGGAAGCUGAAGAGGAGAUUCUACUAGAGAUCACAAUCAAGUAGAAGACUUAGACUUUAAAGAAGGAAAGAUAAAUGCAUGAAAAAUGAGGUACAAACAAUGUAUAGAACUAUAGACAGGAGAGAAUGGAUAUGGACUUGCUUCUUUGGGGGAAAAAAAAGAGGUAUUUAAAUCAGUUUUGAAAGAUUAUUAAGAUUCUAACAAGUGAUUGGAAUGCAGAGAAAUCAGAUGUAAAUUUGAUUUACAUCACUGCAGGCAAAGAGCAGGGGUAACACUAAAUUGCCAUGUUCUCCAUGUCAGAGACCUGUGUUGCAGAAAAUACUGUGUACCUUGAUCUGAAAUAACCACAUCCGGGACACUUUAGUAUUGUCCUGUAUUCUUUUCAGAAUAUCAGAACUCCUCCUGGCCCUGCAUACUGCUGUCACAUGGAAUAAUAUAAAUUCAUCAAAUAAAUCAUAUAUGUCCACACUCUCAGGCCUUCUGUACCUACCUGUGUCUUUUAUGUCCAUAAGUCUGCUUUCUCCCUGCCUUUUUAUCCACAGAACAUACCUACAUUUACCUGGCUAUUUAUUAGGCUUUAAUGACUCAUUGUGGGAGUUCUGUCUUCUGAGAAGCAUUGUCCGAUGCUACCAUCUCAAGUUUAAAUUAAGUACCCCUCCUCAGGGGCACAGAGCCCAUCGCUGUUACCUCUAUCACAGCACUUACUUCAUGCUCUCUCAAUCCACAGGUUUUUCAGAUCUCCUCCUUUAGACUAUAAUCUUCUGAUAGCAAAGACAAUAAUAUCAAACACCUGGAAGAGAGCCUGCCCUGCAGAAGACCCUGAUUCAAUUAAUAUUUGUUGACUGGGAAACAUUCAGAUAUAAAAAUGUAGAAAAAAUGUCUAUAGUCAGCCGGGCUCAGUGGCUUAAACCUGUAAUCCCAGCAUUUUGGGAAGCCAAGGCAGGCAUAUGGCUUGAGCCCAGGACUUCAAGACCAGCCUGGGCAACAUGGUGAAACCCUGUCUCUCCAAAAAAUAAAAAUACACACACACACACACACACACACACACAUAUGUAUGUACACACAAAACUUAGCCAGCAUGGCGGCAUGUGCCUGUAGUCCCAGCUACUUGGGAUGCUGAGGUGGGAAAAUCACAUGAGCCCAGGGAGGUCAAGGCUGCAGUGAGCCAUGACAGCACCACUGCACUCCAGCCUGGGCAACAGAUUGAGACUUGGUGUCAAAAAAAAAAAAAAAAAAAAAAAAAGAAUGUCUCCGAAUAAACUUGGACUAUCAUUUUCAUUGUGCAGCAAAAUGAGUAGGUGAUUGUACACACCUAACCCAUACAUUCUGUACUUGUCUCUCCCCUUCACUUUUCAUAUCCUUAAUUAGCAGAGCCUACCAAUCUUUUUUUCUAAAUAUAUUUUUUAUUAUUUCCACUUCCAUUUUAUCUCCACUAUCAUUGCCUUAAUAUAGGACUUCAUUUUUCACUUGGACAAUAUUGCAAUAACCUCUUAACUCGUCUCCCAGUUGCAAUAAAUGUCUAUUAAAUUUAAGUGGUUGAAAUGCUUAAAGUAACACUCCCUAUUUUGAAAAUAAAUCAACUAGCAAGUACCUGCUGCCCACCUACAAUAUGUUCCAAACUUAUUAUGUGCUAUGAGGGAGUCAGGAGAAGCAGAGCAUACAAACUUCCACUUUACCCCCAGGACACUAUAAUGUGGGCAUGGAGAACUGAAACUGUGCUUCUCAAAGUACAUGAUGCAUGCAAGUCACCUAGGGAUGUUACUAAAAUACUGAUUCAGUAGGUCUUGGGUAAGGCCUGAGAUUUUGCAUUUCUAACAAAUCCCCAGGAGACGUGGGUGCCACUGGUCUGUAGGCCAUCCUUUGAGUGAAAAAAUAUUAAAAUCCAUUAAAUACCAUAUGACAUACCUCAUAGUGAAGAUUCUAAGUGCAGGCAGACUUCAUGAAAGUAGUAAAUGAUACAAUGGAAAACUCUCCAUGUAAGAGAAGAAUGGACACUGAGAAAAUGCAAGCCCAUUCCCUGUUCCUACUCAGCUUAUAAGAUGACUCACUUCUCAUCUUCUCUCUAAAGCCUUUCUGACACAAUCUCACCUUCCUGGCACAAUCUCACAUUGCCGCUGUCUCUCUACCCCUUUCUAUUCAUGCUCUAAAGUAUUAAUACAUUCAGAAAGAUCUUUCUAAAAUACAAAACCGACUUUGCCACUCUUAGGCUUAAAGUUCUUUAAUUCCUAUCACCUGCCAUUUAAAUUCCACAAUGGAAGGCCCUUCCCAAUUGGCCCCUUUCCUGACUCUCUAGACUCAAUUUCCACCACUUCUACCACAUGUCACCUGCAUUCGCCCAGCUUCACCACACUCUUUCUUACCUCUGCUUGUCAUAGGCCAUUGCCUGUGCCUGGCACCUCCCGUCCCCAUUGUCUACUAGGCAACAGUGCAUCCAUUCUUACUGGAAGCUCAAAAGUUCCCUCCUCCACAGGGCCUGCCUUCUCCUGCCAGGCAGAGUUAUGUAUUUCAACGCCUUUUUGAGUCCAUAGCAUAUAAAACAUUAUUGAGUUCUAUUUAUCUCUACUGAUUUCAGUACUCCCAAGAGAGCCCCUAUUUUGCAAGGAUCUGAAUCUCAUCUUUCUUUAUACCUUCUACCCAUAUUCAAGAUGUGAAAGAUGUUUUAAUAACUGUUGGUUAAAAGAAAAAAUAAAUAAAUAAAUCCGAACUAGCUAUUUACUCAAACAUCCCUUUUUACCAAGAAAUAAUUUAUGAUGGCACUAAUAAACAAAACCAAUGUGUUCUGUGAUGAGAUUUCAGUACACAACAGAAGUAAAUGUUAGGGUGAAGGGAAAGGAGAAAAAGAAGACAGAGGAAGAAAAUGCUAAGAAACACUGCAAUGAGGAAAAUAGAUAUUUACUACUUACAUGUUAAGUCUUUUCUGAGAACACACAUGUGCACACAUACACAACAUUCAUAAUUUAAACUGCCCUAAAAAGUCCAACCAAAUUUUAGCUCAUUCCCAGAAAGCAGUAGACAAGACAGGAAAGUGUGUUAAUACUCCUUCUUUUCCAGUCAUUAUUCACCUAGGUACUGGAAGUUGUGUCUCAGAUAUUGGAUUGAAUGGAAAUGAAAGAGGGUCUCUUGGUGAGAGCAGUCAAUGUUCCUCCUAUUUACAGAUGGCAUGGCUGUGCUUACGGACAAUGUAUGUGAAUUAUUAUUUUUCAGUUGAAAGCAAAACUCAACCAUGAAUUUCAGGGAGCAAUUAAAAGAUAAUCCUGAAUACAAAUAAAUCAUGCCCCACAACUCAUAAGAAAGCCACAUAAAUGGUCAUUUGGUAAAAGAGAAGGAUAUCUUUAGAAUUUUCUUUAGAACAUUGCUCAAUAAAGAAAUACAAAAGUCAAUAACACUAGACAAAAAAUAUGCAGUAAAACCAAUGAAAUAUUUAAAAGACUGUCAUUUAUACUGAAAAAAAUAGACCAUCAACAUUAUUGUUACUCAGAAAUCUCACAUUCUUAAUAUAAAAGAAACUUGGCAAUGAGUAAAAUGAUUAAAAAUUAUUCAGUGUGUCAAAAAACACUCAGCCAAAUAUUAAUGUAAAUAGAAAUAUCAAUAAAAAAGUACUCAUUAUAAAUAAUAAUGUCACAUUACAUAAAGAUUAACUUCAGUAUUACAUCAAAUCAUUCUUCUAAAGCUAUUUAUAUUAAAUGUCAUUUAAUUCUCCCAAAAUUUUAAUACUUUUCUAUAUCAUCUUUUGUGUCCAUAUUUUUAAUCCCCAGAUAAAAAGUGAGUGCCUACCAGGUUAUAAGUUCAAUAUGUGUUGAAGCUGAAUAAAAGUGAGUUAUCAUCAGCCACUAUAUCGAUCAGUCAGCCAUAUUUUCCAGAGCAUCUGCCUACAUGCUCAGCACUGCUCUGAGAGAAAUAGAAGAAACAGGGAGCCUGAAGUUGGUCUCCUUUCCUGGGCAUUAAGGUGUAGUCAGGAGACAAUACUAAAUGCUAACAGUGGGAUCAGUGAGAAACGGUGGAAGCUAGUUUAUAAGCUAUAUCAUGUAGUUCAUGAUAAAAUUGCUGUAUAGGAUUCAGAGUAGAAAAGUUCUACCCAGACAUGGUCUCAUGAGUUGGGGAUGGAAAGAUUAAAAAGAUGUCCAAAGUAGCAGGCAUGGAGUGAAGUCCAGAGUGGACAGAUCUGAGGAGAUGUUGCACUCUUCAGAUUCAGGAAAAAAUAUGACCACAGAUCCAAGGGCAGGAAUAAUAAUGCACAGCCGGGCCCUUGUAACACAACUAAUAUAGGAAUGGGACCCUAUAGAGCUGCAACUGCACAGCCUGCACAGUAUGCAAAGGCCCUGCUAUACAGCUUUCUCAACCUGUUGUGCUGUUUUUGGCUUCCUUGAACCCACUUGAUUCCAUCCUUUGAGACUCAAAUGUUAUUGUCUCUGUGAAGCCUUUCCCUUUCCCAACCUUCCGUCACACUCUACAUGUAUUAACAAUUUAUCCAUAUGCCAUAAUUACAUAUCAAUAAUUGCAUGUAAUCUUUAUCCCACCAGUUCACUCCUCCUCAUCCCACACAUUGUCUAAAUCAGCAGUGACCAACAGAACUUUCUGUGAUUAUAGAAAUAUAAUAUCUGCACUGUCCAAAACAAGAUCCUCUAGACAAAUACGGCCACUGAACGCUUGAAAUGUGGCUGAUGUGACAGAGAAUUCAAUUUUAUUUAUUUUAGAUUUAAAUUAAAAUUUAAAUAACAGCAUCUGGCUAGUGGCUACUGUACUGGACAUAUGGUUUUAUACUAUGAACUUCUUGAAGGCAAGAAUGAUGUAUUAGCAUCCAUAUACUUUAGUAUAGUCAAUCAUAGUAUGUACUCAGUAAAGUUUUGUUGAAUAAAUGGCCAAAUAUGAAUGAAUCUUAGUAUAUAGUUGACAAAGUAAUGAAUAUAAAGAUCAGACAUAUGAAAAAGUAACAAAUUUAAUGGUGUCUAAAGAUAAUUAUUGAAAGAUGAGAAGAGAAAUAGUGUGAUUUGAAUGUAGUCUGCUUUUUAAAAAAAUGUCAGUAAAGGUACCCUAAAAUAGAAAUUAACCAAAAAAAAACAAAAACAAAAAACCUGUUGAAAUGCUGAUACUCUAUCUUCUUUAUAUGUUUAUGUUUUGCACUAACUUUUUCCACUAUUUUAUACUGUCUUAAUUAUAUCUAAGUCUUCAAACACUAGACUGUGACCUCCUUGAAGCAGGUACUUUUAUUCCCACUGUGUACCCAGUUCCAAAUGUAAGCUUAGACCACAAUAGGUACCCAAUAAAUUUUACAGGGAGAGUGAAAUGAGUGAUAAGACAGGAAAUAAACUAUUUUAAUAAAACUAGCAGAGUUGAUGUUCAGAAAGAAAAGAUAGCUGUUAGAAAACAUCCUAAGUGACUGUGAACAAUAAGGCAUUCUGCAACAUCUACUUCAUGUGUGCAUUUAUGCCUUGUGUUUGAGAAACCUGUGUUAUUUCAAAUAAUGUUUUCCUAAAACAAACAUGACUGUCUUAUUCUCCCUGUCUCCUACCUGCCAUUCUAUAAAGUCCCAUUGCUUUUAGCUUUAAAUUUGGUUUCAGCCUCUUUGACUCUUUUACUAUUUUCUUUUAGUAUUUCCAUUACCUUAAAAGAGUGAGUACAGUUGUCUUCACUUUCUCGUGGUAGAAAGUUAACAGUAUAGAAGUAUGAAAAUGUCACCAAAGACUAAUCAGAACAAAUUGCAAGAGUUUUUCCUAAUGUCUCUGCUUCAGACCUACCAUGUAGAUUAGCAUAUCAGAUUUAUCAUUCUGAUACAUCAGAGUCUGGUUUAUAUUUGCCAGCCAGUGUCACUUCUCAGAGCACUGUUUUUUACUCUGAGUCAGAACAGGUUUCUGUGAUAUCUCCCUUAAGAAAUGCCAAGUUUGGCCACCAUCUAUAUCUUUUUCCCUUUCCCUGGGUAGCUCAGAAAUCAAUAAAAGAGCAGGUUUAUGAUUGCUGAUGCUUAAAUUAUACUUGUCAUUCUAAAGAUAUUUAUUGCACACUUACUAUGCAAAACUGUGUUCUAAGUGCUUUAAAGGAAAUUGAGAUGAAUCAUGCAUGAACCUGACCUCCAAGAAUAUGGUCAUCACUGAAAGAUAAGAUACAGGUAUAAUAGAUAAAAAGUAGCAAUUGCUAAGUACAAUUAUCCCUCCAUAUCUGAGUGGGAUUAGUUCUAGAACUCCCUCCAGAUACUACAUUGCCAUGAUGCUCAAGUCCCUUAUAUAAAUGGCAUAUUAUUUGCAUAUAACCUAUACACAUCCUGUAUACUUUAUAUUAUCUCUAGAUUAUUUAUAAUACCGAAUACAAUGUGAGUACUAUGUAAAUAAUUGUUAUACUUUAUUUUCUAUUUGUAUUAUUUUUAUUGUUGUAUUAUUAUUUUUUAUUUAUUCAUUUUUUGGAAAUUUUCAAUCAAUGAUUGGUAGAAUUCACAGAUGAAGAACCCUCAGAUAUGGGGGUCCUACUGUAGAGCAUAUGGAUUUAGAGCAGCCUUGGAUUUGUAUUUUGACCCCCAUAUUAGGAGUUACAUGACAUUAAACAAAAUACAUUAACCUCUCUGUGCUUUACUUUCCUCUUUUGCAAAAUAAUACCAGGUUUUGUCUCUGGAUUAUUGACUUAUAAUCUGGAUGAACCCAAAACCCCUGGUGGAGGAUGAGAGAGACCAAGCAUGUCAAUACCUUAACAUUGUUUUGUCCCUGGCACACACAUGAAAAUGCUUAGCCAAUGCCUGAUUAUAAGCAAAAUGCUUUCAGAGUUUAGAGAGAUAAUGCUUUUGCUGUAUGGAUGACGUGGAUUCUGUCUGAAACUGAAAGAUUGUUGGAUUUAGACAUAGAAAAUGCAAAGUCAAAAUCUGAAAAGAAGAGUAUCAACUAUCCACAAUAAUUCACAAGGCCAGGAGAUCGGAAAUUAUUAAUUUUCUUCACAAUUAUGUUUAUUGAAACAUUGUCUAAAAUCUAUGAAGUACCAUGCUAGGUGCCUUAGGGAAGAAUGGCACAAAAUAAAUGGUCUCUACUCUCACAGGAGUCAUUGAACUAGUAGAGGUUCCUGGGGGAAUCACGCCACCUUUAACCUACAGCAUGUUUUUCUCAUUGGUAGAAGUAAUAUUGUGGGUUUGUUGGGAGGGUGGACUGCUAGAUGUCAGGGACUGUGUUUUAGUUAACUUUGCCUCCACGUUAAGCACAACUCUUAGCACAUAGUAAGUACUCAUUACAUGUUUAUUGAAUGAAUCAAUCAACAUAUUUUGCAUGAAUAUGUUCUAGUGCUUACCCAAUAGUAAAAUUAAGACUUUUAUAAUAAUUCUUAAAAAUAGCUACUUGAGUUCUACACUGUUAAUACCUAAAUGAUGUUUAUCAAAGAGUGUAGCGCUUCAAAGGCAAACUUAACAACUGCUGAAUGAUUUUAAUCAUGAAAUAACAUUCAUGAUAAUAUUACCACAUUUGUGUAACACUUUAUACCCUUCUAAAAACGUCUUUUGGAUAAUUUUCCUGGCUUUUGGUUUUUGUAAUUUGUACGUUUAUGAAAUGUGAUAUGUUUGAAUUUGAGUAAACUCUGCUCACCUAGAAUGUUUAGACAAAUGAAAAAGUAUAAAAUAAUAACCAAUAAUAGUAAAAAUCAUAACAUUGAUGACAAAACCAGGAGCUUCCAUUCACUGCGCAGUUGCUGUGUUCCAGAGCCUAACUACCAGUGCUUUACAGGUGUCCUCUUAUUUAGUCCUCACAAUAAUCCUACUUAACAGGAACUACUGCAAGUUCCCUGCUACAGUGAAGGAAACCCAGAGUUAUAAAUCUUAGAAAGAAUGUCAAAGAUCAUAAAGCAAAGAAAUAGCAAGACCAGGAUUGAAACCCAAGUUUGUCUUCUCCCAAAGUCCAGGCUCUUCACACCCUACUACUAAACUGCUACCUACUCCUAAAUAAUGACAACAGAGACUAUUUAUAAACUCACCCUUUUUUUCCAGGUAUUAGACCUUUAGGGAAUCAUUUAUCCUCAAAAUAACACUAGAAGAAUAUAGGUUUUGAUAUUCUAUUUUCCAGAUGAGAAAACUGAAGCUUAAAGAAUCUUGGCUGCUUGCCCAUGUUUACAGAACUAGCCAUGGCAAAUAGAGAAUAGACCCAAAUUUAUUUAAGAGGCAACAGGGUCCUUAAUCACUAUCUUCUAUCAAUGGUAAUUAAGUGUUUUGGUUAGGAAAAAAAUCAUUGUAUUUAGAGUAAGUUCUUACCAUAGUUAAAAUGAAAUAAUGUACUUACACUUAACAUUAAAGUCACACCAAAUAUAAUUUCCUCUUUUCACAAUGAUUAGAAAGGCACUUCAGAAUCUUGAAGUGCCUCAUUAUCAUGCACAUAAUUAGCAUAUAAUAAUAUUUUUAAAGGGUGGGUGUUUGAACCUUUGGACCAUUUAGCUUCUGGACAUGUGGGAGUUUGUUUUUAAUGUUUUCCUUUACUAAACAAUUUCUAGCUAAAUUAUCUGGAAAUCAGGUCUGAAUGAAAGACGCAGAGCAAAGUAUACUCUUAACCCAACCCCUAUGCCCUCAGAUGAGAGAAAUAAACCCAUCUUUCCUCAGUGGAUAGAAGAAUUAUGGAAGAAGGUGAGCAUAGCUCCAGUGUUUUCAACAUCUUAAGUUACUCAUCAACAUCUAUUUCAUUUCAUUAAUAAUGAAUUCAACCACCAACCAAUUUGAGUAAUUGUCAGUAAUCAGAGAAUGUUUCCCCAACCUUCAAAUCUAUGUCAUGGAAGUGAAAAUUUCCCUAGCGCCAUAACAGAGGAGAAAAUCUUAAGUUAUAUAAUGUGAAAAUAUUUGCCAUUUUAUUUGAGGUACUGGGAUAUAAAUUAUAUAUAUGUCCAUCAUUCUUCAGCAUGUUUCCAAAUCUGCAGUGUAUUGUAUUUUUUGCAACUAAUAGAACUCAUUACACUAAUAGUCUAGUAUUAUGUAAAUGCAUUUUAUCCAAAUAUCUAGUAUCCAUAAGUAGUUUGUUCUCUAUAUCCCUAAUGUAAUAUAUCAAACAAUAACUCAUUUGUCAAAGGGAGACAGUUCAUUAAAAUUCAACAACUGUUUGGCCAGGAUAAAACAGCAACAGUAUAAAAAUUGAUGUUGCAAAACUUAACAAAUGAGGGAAUAAGGGAAGUGAGAAUAAGGAAAUUGCAGGCCUGCCCUCCAGGGCCAUUUUUGGGCCACUUGUCUGAAUUUUAAUAUUACAAUUGUUUUACAAAAAGUCUCCAAGUUAUUAGGCUGGGAGGGAAGCCAAUUUACAGCUAGGUGACUUGAAUAUCAGGGGCAUUCAAUAAAUGAGAACAUGAUAUCACUUAGGACAUAGAGUGGAAAAGGUACAACACUUGAGCACUGUGCUACAAUUCAGUUUUUAAAAGUGAGUUAUUAUAUGACUUAGCACAUAUCAUCCCUUGUUGAGUUGUAUUUAAGUAGCAUAGUGAAUAAGAGUUUUAGACUGUUUUGUUUGUGUUUUCAAAUGUAGUAUUUGCUCCAUAUUUUUUUAAAGCAAAAUACCAAGCAUAGAAAUAGCACCUACCAGAGGUUUAGAUAAUUUGAAAAGCAAAGAACAUGAACCUGUUGAUGAGCUGACACCCAUUCUAUCGCAAAACAGUUUUAGGAAAGGUGAAAAAAAUAAAAACAUGCAAUUUUUGAAGGUGCCUGGAGAAGUACAUUUAUCAUUUGGGAUGUAUCUAUGAAAUCUGCUUAAAAUUAAAAAUAAAAGAUUUUUAAAUAUUUUUAAAAUUAAACUUAUUAGACUUAUUGUAAAAAUAUUACACUUAUUGAUACAACUAUGUUCACUGAAAUCACUUUAUUCAAAAAUUACUAUAUUAACAUAUGCAUGUAUAUUAAAAUAUUAGACUUAUUGAUAUAACUAUGUUCAUCAAAAUUGCCUUAUUCAAAAAUUACUAUAUUAACAUAUGCAUGUAUAUACAUUUAAGAGGGAAAGUUCUUUAUGUUUACAUGCAAGUGCUGCUUUGUACUUAUACAUUAUUUACUUAUUAGCUGUAUAUAACUUAACUGAAUAACUUCUCAUCACUUUAAUAUUACCUACAUACUUCUAGAACUUUUUGUUUCUAAACAAGUUUUUCUCCAUAUGGUGUUAUCAAGGAACAUCAUGUUUGACUCUUCAUAUAGCCAACAAAAACCCUGAUUUUCAAGAAAUCUGUCUUUCCAAAGGCAAAUACGAAGGGUUUGACUGGGGGCCGAGAUCUCUUAUAGCUGAGGUUUUAUACUAUUCUCUCCUCUUUCUAAUGGCAGUAGUGUGUGCGUGUGUGUGUGUGUGCGUGUAACUUUCAUUUUCCCACAUGCACCCAAUGUAUUAAAUUUAUUCUUUCAGUUAGCAGAAGCCUUUCCAUAGGAUAAAAAUGACAAGCAUUAUGAAAGGCAUUCAAAGUUCCCAGGCUUCUUAGGCCCAUUCGAGGAUCAAGUAUUCCUUCAAAAUCCACUUUCAAGAUUCCACAAGUUUAUUGCAAGAUAUUCAUAUGUAAAUUAACAGACCUGUGUAGUGAUCUCCCUAACAUAUUUUUGCUCUAUCAAAGUUCUACUUGCUGUUAGAAAGUAGCAGUUAAUGUCACAACUACUGUUCUGUUAUGCAUGCGAGGGAAUCAAAGUACAGUAAUCAAAGUACAGUAGAUAAUUAUUUUUUAGUACAUAGUAGAGUGGUAUAACUAAGCUUUCUUUUAAGCUGUUAGUCAAAUUACACAGCUAAUAAGCAAAAGACAAACGAGCAAAGCUAUAUUUGCUACACUGUUUGUCUCUUAACGGAGAUCAAAGAAUGAAGCUGGUUUGCAACUCUGUGACCUGUCAUUCUGUGAAAAGUGUGUCUCUCGCCAAAAAUGAAACUACAAAUCACAUGCUGUUUGAUGGUGUGCCUGUGCUUGUGUGAACAGGCCACCACAUUCAAGCUAUGAAGAAGCUGCUAACAGGUGUCAUCUGCUUUGCAAAAUUACAGUUUCCACAAAGCACCACGAAUUGGGAUCAUUAAGAAUACCCAGAUGCUGUAUCCCAGGCUUCAGGGCUUAAACAUGUACUUCAGAUUUUCAGGUUGUUUUGUUUGUUUGUUUGUUUGUUUGUUUGUUUUUGUCUUUGUUUUCAGUUUCAAUGAUCUAUCUCCAAAUGAGAUACUCUGAGUGUUUGAGCUUUGCACCUAUCUAUGAAAUUUACUUUAAGUAGGUUCCUUAUUCAAUGCUGAAAAUUAGGUCAGCUAGAACUUCUAGUCCAUUUGACUUCUUAUCUAUUAAAACUUCUUGUUUGACAGAAGUCUAUGAAAAGAAAUGAACAAAUAUGAAUGUGACUUAUGCAAAGCCAAUAAAAUUAUACUUUAAUCUAUUAAGCUUAAACCCCUGAAAUUCCAUCAUAUUCCGUUGUAUAUUUCCGGAUAGCCAGGGCAGAUACAUGUUUUGUUUUUGAUAGUGUUAAAAGCUGAAAAAACAUUGAUUUGUUUGAAGAAAAAAAAACAUAAAAGGCAUGCUGUAAUGAGAUUUUUGAAACACAUUAGAGAAAUUUUAACUUAAAAAAUUCAAAAUAUUAAACAUAAAACUCAUUUACUCUAAAUUUAUUAUUUGAAAAAUGAAUGGAUUUAAUCAAGUAACCAGGAUUUUUUGCGUGCUUGAUGGCUAAUAAUUUCUUUGUGUGCAAAUUACCUUUCAACUAGUUGCUUCGGUGUUCUAAGAUAUAAUUAAAGAGAUUAAAUGCUUAUAGAAAUCAGAGAUUCUAUGCAGAUGUUAUUACUCAUAAAUUUUGUUUUCAACAAGUUAACAGGGCAAAUACUUUUAUUUAUCUAUGCAUUCAAUAUUCAUUCAGUAAGUUUCCACUUUGUGCUUAGCAUUGGACUGGCUCCCAGAGAAAUGUAUAUGUAAUAAAAACAAUGUAGGUCCUGUCACGAUUUACUGCUGCUUAGUUUGUGUGCGUGUUUCUGUCUUGUCUUUUCUAUUGGCCUAUAAGCUCUUGGGGCUAGUUAUAUAGCAUCAUGAGUUCCCCAAAGUGCUUCUCACAAAGAGCUCAAUUAAUAAAUAGUUUUAUUUGCCUAUGAAAAGCAUCUGUUAUAACUUACUUUCCUUGCCUCAUUUUUUCCCCAAUUUCCCUCCCUAGCAACUUCCACUCUGUCCACACUGAACUGUUCAUUAUUCCUUGGAGUGAUUUGCAUUUCCAUAUAUCUGGGCCUUUGCUAUUACUAAACUCCUGUGUGUUUUGUUUUGUUUUUUAAUGUCGUUUAUCCAUACACUUAACUCCUCCUUCAAACCAAGCAGAAGUAGUUCUCUUCUGAAUGUACCACUAUUAAAGCACUUAUUACAUUGGUAUAUAACUAAUUGUCAGCUCCUGUCACUAAACUACUAAAAGUUUGGUAUGAUUUUAUUUUCCUCUUUGUAUCUGUAGUGCCAUGUAAGACCUUUUAUAAAGGUGACAUAUAACAGUUGGUACAAAGGAACAAAAUAAAAUGGCAUACAAUAGUUUUAAAAAGUUUACUAGAGCUUUGUCUAACAAUUAGUCAUUGCUUACUAUUGAGCAGGAUAAUAAUGCCUUGCGACUGCUUCCAAAUCCCUCUUUCUCUGAUCUCUCUGCCCUUCAACUUUUCAAGAGUACCUUUUCCAUAUACUCUCUACCUCAAAAGCUUUUCACUUAAAACCCUCCUGCCAAAGUUGGGAGAGGGAUUAUUGGUGUAGUGAUGGUACUUUUUCUGGGAGUAUUUGAAUCCAAACAAGAAAUAAAUUACCUUAAACCAAAAAAGUAGGUUUUGAACUGCGAGGUUUCAAGGAGUAUCAGAAACAAAGGAAACAGUUUUGUCAGAGGCCACACACACAAAUCCAAAAUCUUCUUACGACUCCAUUGAUCUUCGUCCUGUGCCUCUUGAUGUUUUCAUGAAAGAUGGAGGAGUUGCUAUUACAUGAGAAAUAAGCUGUUACUAAGAUUAUUCCAUUCUACCAUGGCAAAGUAGUGCAGAUGGCCAUAUGGGAAAGCUGAAUAAAUAAUUAUUUUAUAAAGAUAAAACUAAAAAUAGUAUCCAUCUCUCAUUCCUGAAAGUAGCAUCACUGUGCUAUCUUGUGUAAGAUUACAUUUUUAAGGCUUGGUUUAAAAUAUUUUCAUUACAAAUUCUUCUCUGACAUUGUUUAAAAUAUUUUCAUUACAAAUUCUUCUCUGACAUUUGUAAAACAUUUUCUAUUUGUUUUACAAAUUUUAUUUUUAAAAAUUAAUUUAAAAGCCAAUAGUCACUGCAGAGCUUAGAAUAAAUUUCAUCAUUUUUCUUUAUCUACAAUUACCAAGGGAACACCAUAGCAUACCAUUGCUAAAUGGUGUUUUCAUUCACUAGAUGACCAUCCUCCUCUACUUAUGUUAUUUUACUACUAAAGAAACUGCAAUAUUUUUUUAUUGUGAUAUAAUAUUUAUUUCCCACAUAUUUUCCAAAAGACCAAAAUUUUAAUCAAAAUUUAAGAAACAAUCUCCUGGCCAGGCGCGGUGGCUCACACCUGUAAUCCCAGCACUUUGGGAGGCUGAGGCAGACGGAUAACGAAGUCAAGAGAUCAAGACCAUCCUAGCCAACAUGGUGAAACUACUACUAAAAAUACAAAAAUUAGCUGGGCGUGGUGGUGCACCUGUAGUUCCAGCUACUCAGAAGGCUGAGGCAGGAUAAUCACUUAACCUGGGAGGCGGAGGUUUCAGUGAGCUGAGGUCGCACCACUGAACUCCAGCCUGGAGACAGAGCUAGACUCCGUCUCAAAAAAAAAAAAGAAAAAGAAAAAAAAGAAACAAUCUCCAUCAUUCUUUUGUGACAUAAUCCACCUAUAUACACUUCUAACUAAAUCAAGAUAUUUAGAUUAUAGUCUAAGUUAAACAAACCCAGAUGUACAAAAAUCAUCAGGCUAUUUGUAGAGAAAGUAUUGUUUUGAUAAAUAUAGUUAUCUCAAAAAAAAGCAAAAAAAUGAGGAUAUGUUUAAGAAGUAAAUAAACAUUUGUGUGUGUGUGUAUAUAUAUAUAGACAUAGAUAGUUACAGAUAUAACAUUAUCUUUUAGACCCAUAAGGAAUGUUGGGAUAAAGAAAAUAUAACCUAUUCACUAAAAAAAAAAAAAAAAGGAAAUGAGACCCAGAAAGAAAGUUUCAGUGAACCAUUCAAGAUUUUUUUUUCUUUUUUCUUUUUUCUUUUUUUUUGAGAUGGAGUUUCAUUCUUAUUGCCCAGGCUGGAGUGCAAUGGCACGAUCUUGGCUCACCACAACCUCCGCCUCCCGGGUUCAAGUGAUUCUCCUGCCUCAGCCUCCCGAGUAGCUGGGAUUACAGGCAUGCACCACUACGUCUGGCUAAUUUUGUAUUUUUAGUAGUGAUGUGGUUUCUCCAUGUUGGUCAGGCUGGUCUCGAACUCCCGACCUCAGGUCAUCCCCCUGCCUCGGCCUCCCAAAGUGCUGGGAAUACAGGCAUGAGCCACCGCCCCCAGCCAAAGAUCAUGUUUUUUACUCACAGUCAUAGCUAGACCCAAACACAGAAGUCUUGACCUUUAAACUAGUUCCCUUCCCAUCAUAUAUAGUAAUUGUUGAAGAGUUAUGUUCAAAAUAGAAUAUACAAGCAAGUUUAAGAUCUCUAUUUUAGAAAAUUGAAUCUUUGAAAAAUAUGUUUGAUGAUAUUUCAGAGGCAUUAUUAACAUCAAUUAUCACUGUAUUAAUAAAAUUUACAUUUAAAAAGUCCAGUAAGUAGACUUAUGAAUAAUGAAGAGUUUAUUAACUACACUCAAAGAGACGAUCUGAAAAAACAGACUAAUAAACCAGAAAAAUAAUUAGAUUAGGAAGCUAAUCUGUGUAUGAGAUUGCUCCUCAAACCAAAUCCACUCUGAAUUUGGACUUGGACUUAGUGAGGGAUUAGAGAAAUCUCUCUAGGGGCCAAAUUCAUAAUCCAUGGCAGCCAAUGCAGCCGAAGUGUCUGUGCACAAGAAAUAUUCUUGCCUGACUUGCAAUAUUAUCUUGCUGCUACAUGCUUCACUAAGUUGGAAGAGAUGCCGCUAAAGAGCAGGGGGCACAGGAAACCUGAUUCAACUUUUGGAAACCAUUAGAGAAGCAUGCUGAAGUUUGGAGAAAAAAAAACUGCCUUCUUCAGGGGAAAUUAAGUAUAAUCAGAGGUCAAGGUAGAAAUUUACUAACAUAGAUUGGGCAACCAUUUACAUGGAUUAGGGCAUGGACUCACUCCAGUUUCACCAAAUGCCACACCUGGAGAGUAAACGUAACUCUUAGGCAUCAGUCACCUGGAGUCCCCGGGCUCCUUAAUGCUCUGUCAAGAUUGAUGAGGAUAAAGCAGGAGGGGCACAGAUUUAAGCCUAUAAAUUGAAUCUUAGGUAAGCCUAUAGUCUUAGACAGACUAUAUUUUAGAAGACAGAAUCUGGCACACUUUAAAAUCUGAUUUUUAGAAAUGUUUUUAUUAGUUUAGUACAUUCACUUAACAAGCAUAAUUUUAUUCACAAAUGCCUAUCAUGUGCCUGGCAAUAGGGUCUGAAUUCUUCAUAACCCAGAACUUUGUCAUACUCAGUUUUUAGCCUCAGAAACUGACAUAAAUUUAUAGUUAUUGAUAAAUCAGAAGAUAAUUCUGUACAUCUAUUUUUUUUCUCUUUUUUUCGCUGCAUUGAUAGUCUGAAGAUCAAAUUUCCCAAGCUCUCCCAAUAGUCAUGCAAAAUUAUACUUACUUAGAUUUUCUAUUACAUUUAUUUGUAAACUUAAGUUAAAAUCUAUUUUCAAAAGUUCUCAUUUUGAGUUUUAUUCGUCUUGUAUACACUCUGCACGUAAUGUCAUCAAUUAAAAUGAGAAUAUGCUUAGAAAAUCUUUAUAACCAUCUACCAUGGCUAAUGAUCUUAACUUUAAUGCACAAAAUGUUAUUUCAUUGGAAAUUUGGUGCGUUCUUAGAGUGACCCUUGUUUCUGUAACAUUUUCAGCGAUCUUAGAUCAAAAAGCACCAACAAAUAUUUCUAGAUUUGUUUUCUAUAACAAGUACUCAUAUGGCACUUAACUAUUUGAAAAAUAAAUCAGUUAAAUUUUAAAUAAUUGCUAACAAUCAUGCUGUCAUGAUCUACAAUGUAUAGAAAAAAAUAGCUAACACAAGUAGAACUUUGCAUACGCCAAGAUUGUACUUGAAAUGCUUUACAUAUAUUGACUUUAUUCAUCUUUACAUCAACUCUGUAAGAACCAUUAUUAUCCCCAAUAGUAACAUUCCCAAGGCCUUUCAGCUUGCAGUGGUAGAAGUAGGGCUUAACCCCAGAUGGUCAAACUCCAGAGUCUGUGCUUUCAAUAAAUAUUUAAUUUUGUCAAUUUAUAACAAAGUCAUUUGGAGCGUCUCCUGUUGCUGGGAUGCAUGGAUGGCAAAAAUAUCUCUAUCUUUUAGCUAUCACCUUUGCUGAAAUGUUGGGUGGUCCAUGCCCACAGAAGGUGAGAAAGUUUUAUAUGCUUAUUUUUAACAACUAGAACAUAGGAUUUAAAAAGACAAGGGUAAAUUUCAACAAUGUAGUGUAUAUGUUGUCUUCUAAGGAGCAAUAGAAGACAACUCUGACUAUCUUAAGCAAAAGGAAAUGUUUUGGAACAAUAGUGGAAAGCCACAGAAUUACAGGAAGGCUACAGAACCAAGCUUAAAAACUAACAGGAACCAAGCCGUCUUGGUGGAAGAGGAAAAAUAACUAUAGGUAUAGUUUAUAUCAGAUACAGAGUGAAUAAGUGAGCCGUACUAGGAUAAAUGAAUUCCAAAUAUUUUCAGUCUAUUUGCUGCUCUACUCAAGACUUUAUAAAAGGAGAAUGGCUUUCUUGAGCUACGGUACUUAACCUCAAAAAAAAAAAAAAAAAAAGGAGAAUCCAGUUAGCCUGGCUUGGGUAACAAUAACUCUUCCUUGACUAAGAGAGGGAGGUGAUUGGAACGCAGCCCUGCCAGUCUAUGUUCAAUGAGGACAAUACUUUUCUAAAUGCAACUGAGGCUGCUCUUAGAAAAUAAAAAUAGGUACGGGCAGUCAAAAACCCACAGACAUCCAUGGUUGUGACUUUCAAAAUAAUUCCCAUUAUCUCGUGUGUGUGUGUGUGUGUGUGUGUGUAUGUAGAUAAGUUAAUCUGUCCUAAAAACUGCUUUAAAAUCAUAUUUUGUUAAGAUUUAUUUCUGAUUAUAACAGUAACACAUAUUUACUGUAGAACACUUGGAAACUAAAUGUGAAAAGUCACUUACAAUCCCAAGAACGAUCUAGUAUUGACAUUUUGAUGUUAUUCUUUUUGUCUUUCUACAAGUAGUUAUACAUACACAUAUAUCUAUAUACUCUAUACUAAAAUUUGAGAUGGUUCCUGUACUUUUGUGUUGUACAUUUGUCACUUAGUUGAUUGUUACUAUGUUUAUAUUAUUAAUCUCUAAGAACAUGAUUCCAUGAAAUCGAUAAUCAUCUAUAAUAUAAUCAUUCUACAUUGUUGUACCUUUAGGUUGGUAAGUAAUAAUAGUAGUAACAGAGAAGAAAAUAAAACAGCUAAUAUUUAUCAGGUAUGUAUUGUAGGUCAGAUACUCUGUGGCAUGCUUUACGUGCAGUUUUAUUUUACUAAAGCAGAAACUAAAGCUCAGGGAGAUAAAUUUCCCCAAGGUCAAAGAGCUAGUGACUAUAGAGUUUGGAUUUGAGCCCAGAUACUCUGGAUAGCCUGUGUUCUUGGUAGCUAUAUCUUUGUGUUAUUACUAAAUAUAUUGUGCUGUACAUCCUUACAUAUAAAUAUUUGCACAGCUUAUUUACUUUAGAUAAAUUCCAAGAUGGGAGAUUGCUGAAUCAAAGUCUAAACAUUUACAAAGCCCUUGAUACAUUUUGCCUGUACAAAUAUACAAAUUUCUAUUUUUUCUGGCAGAAUAUGAGGAUGCUUAUUUCAUAAUAGUCCCAUCAUUGGAUAAAAUUAUUUAAAUUUUCAAAUUUGAAAAAGAAUGUAAUGGGAUCUUAUUUUUGUUCGUUUUCUUUUUUUAAUUGAUAAUGAGACUCACUAUGUUUCAAUUCAUUAUUUUUACCUUUAUGGUAAUUAAGUGACAUUCACUGAACCGUAUUUAUCUGAGUGCCCACACUUCUCUCCCCUGGGGUAUUAUUUAAUGACAAAGGUAAUGUGCAUGAAUCUCUUUUGAUCUGGCCUCAUGACUAGAUUCUUUUUUUUUUUUUUUUUUUUUUGAGACGGAGUCUCGCUCUGUUUCCCAGGCUGGAGUGCAAUGCACUGUCUCAGCUCACUGCAACCUCCACCUCCCAGGUUCAAGCAAUUCUCCUGCCUCAGCCUCCAGAGUAGCUGGAAUUACAGCCAUGUGCCACCACGCCAGGCUAAUUUUGUGUUUUUAGUAGAGACAGUGUUUCCCUAUGUUGACCAGGCUGGUCUCGAACUCCCGACUUCAGGUGAUCCGCCCACCUCGGCCUCCCAAAGUGCUGGAAUUAUAGGCGUGAGCCACCGCGCCCGUCCUGCAUAUUCUUAUAUUCAUUUUAUGGAGCAGCUUUUCUGGGAGUCAAUCUAACCUUGCUACGCUGAGAGUAUGCAAUGCUUUGACAAAGGAUGUAAACCUCAGGUUCCGUAUUUGUAAAAUGAUAAGAAUAACACAUACCCCGUAAGUUUGUUAUGAUGAUUUAAUAAAACAUAAAGGAUUUGAGACAAUGUUCGAUUCAUUUUAAGUGUUUGAUCAAUGUUGGCUACUAUCAGUAAUAAUGGUAAUAGUAGUAAGAGUGAGAGUGGAUAUGUGGCCAAGGUGAUCUUUUCUAAAAAGCACUAUUUUCUAAUUCUUGGGGAUGUGGACUGCCUUACAGAGGGGAGUAAGUCUGAACAGUGUGGAAGAGUUCACCUAGAGCUCACAAUCUAUGAGGGUCCUUUUCAAGAGGAUCCUCUCAAUGGGCAGCUAUCUGCAUCAGUAAAUGAAUACGAUGAUUAGAUAAGGUUUGCCUGAGGUAAGGACAGAGGUGGAGGAACAGUCAAAUACAUGCUCCGAAAGGCUCAGGGAAAGAAACUUUCUCCUCAUUAUCAUUUUGGUGCCAUAAAUUCCAUUUUACUUCUGCAGAAAUUCAGGUUAGAAUGGCAUUUAUUAGAUGCCUAUCAUGUGGGAAGCACAGUUCUACAAGAUUUUCAAACAUCUCAUCUCAACCUUAUAUAAAAAGACACCCAAUGGAUGUGAAAGAAGUAUUGUUACUUACAGAGCAGCAUUAUGUGCAGAGGAGGAAAUAAAUACCAUAGGAGCUUAGUAAUUUACCCAAAGCCCACAGUUAUAGCCAAGUUUGUCUGUCAUUUUUUUCCUGCCAAUGGCCAUUUCUGGACAUCUAGGCCUGGAGAGCUCUCUCUGGAGAGUAGAUUUAACAGGAAAGUUUCAUAGCUCCUCGUGUGAUCAGCAGUGGGAUGCUGGGGUCUAAUAAUAAUGGACCAGGAACCCUGAGUUUGACUUCAGCUCCUUUGCCUCUGCCGUUUACUCAUUUUAUCACUUUGGAAAAAUUACUUAAUCUCCUGUUUCCUCAUCUGUAAAAUGCAGGUAGUGACUGCUACCUUGCAGUGCUAAUGCAAGAAGAAAAGGUAACUGCUGUAAAGUUCCUAGCACAUAAUAGGCAAUGAAUAAUUAAUAAUUAUAAAUAAUGGCUCAGAAUAUUAGCUAUUCAACUUCUAAGGCUUGAACACUGUGUUCUCAACUCUAUAACCUCAAUAUUAAAACCCAAAGCUUGAGUCUUCACAUUCUGACUUAGAAAGACUUCCUUCAUUGUUCCUGUCAUUUAUACACCAAAUGUAAACUAAGUUCUUACUGUGCAUGAAGCUCUUUUUAAAUGCUUUGAGAGGUAAAAGAUUCAUCAGACACAGAUUGUUCACUGGAGGGCCCUACAGUAUAGCAGACGAGGUGAAGCAUGGCCAUCAAUAACUAGUAUCCAGAGUAGAAAGUGGUAAAUGCUUCAAUAGGAUAGAUUUCAUAGAAAGUGCUAUAUGUUGCAGAAAUAUUAAUUUCAACUAAUAAACAUCACAAAGCAAUAAUAUUAACAAUCUUUUCUUUUAUAUGCACUUUUACCUAAGAUCAAAAUUUCAUUUCAACCUCCCUGUCAGCUAUUGAAUGGGGCAACUUUAUCUUACUUGACCCUAAACAGACCAGUUAUUCCUCCUCCACUAUAUAUUUUCCUUAACCAUCAGACACAACUAUUCUAAUUACAUGGAGCAAAAAUCACUGCUAAUCUUUUUCUCUGAUCCUAGAGCAGUAGUGUCCACAGACUAUACAAGUGUGUAUAGCCUGGGGGUAGAAAUUGAGCCCUGUCAGGGCAUGGUUGUUCACGCCCGUAAUCCCAGCACUUUAGAAUGCCGAGGUAGGUGAAUUGCUUGGGCCCAGGAGUUUGAGACCAGCCUAGACAACAUAAUGAAACCUCCUUUCUACAAAAAUUACAAAACAGUAGCUGGGUGUGGUGGCACACACCUGUAGGCCCAGCUACUUGGGAGGCUGAGGUGGGAGGAGAGCAUGAACCCAGGAGGGGAGGCUGAGGCUGCAGUGAACUGUGAUUGCACCACUGCACUCCAGCCUGAGCUACAGAGUAAAACCCUCUUUCGAAAAGAACAGGAACAGGAACAGGAAGGAAAGGAAAGGAAAGGAACGGAAAGGGGGAGGGAGGGAGGAAGGGAGGGAGGCGGGAGGAGGGAAGGUGGGAGGAAUGAAGGAAGGAAGGAAGGAAGGAAGGAAGGAAAGAAGGAAGGAAGGAAGGAAAGGGAAAGAAAGAAAAAAGAAAUUGGGCCCUGUUUGCUCUUGGCCUCUCCUAAUGUCCUAUUUACUUAGAGGUACUGCUGGGACUGAUUCUGGGUCUCCCACCUUCCAGCUCUGCCUUCUCUUUCCUGUACAGCAUCACCCCCUCUCAGCAAUAGGCAGGUUACAAAUUACAGCCUAGUGAUCUAGAAAUUGCAAACUCAAAUGAAUGAAGUCCAAUGAGAAGCAAGGAUCAAGAUGUCAGAAAAUCCUCAAGUUCAUUGAGCUUAAAUAUAAAAGGAGAGGGCAAUAUUGAAACAAAUUUCUUACAUAUAAAUGUCACCCAGCAGCAUUGCCAUCUGCUCCCAAAUAAAGCUUGUGUCUAGAUAAGGAAACCUCAUUUAUAUGGACAAUAUAAUGAAUCUAAGUAUCCAUAAUAGUGUUCCACAGCACUUAUUUCCCUCUCACCAUGGUUCUCCUUUCCCUAAUUUGCCCUGACCUUUUUAGGUGAAGUUUCUUAUUGAAGGCAGAUUUUUUUCCUUGUGUUCUCUUUAUCAUUCAAAUUUUCUUUCAUGCAUUUCUCUGUGUACUUCUUAUUCUUUAAUCCUUAUUUCUUUUUCUUAUGCUUUCCUCUCUUCCCAUUUCUUCCUCCUUCUUUCCUUUUUUCUCCUUUUAUGCUCUCAAUUCACUUCUUUAUAUCUCAACAUGUCCCCGUCUCUCUAAGUCUUUAUGUCUCUCUACCUUUCAUCUUAUCCCUCUCCGUUGAAAUGUGUUUUCUGUGCACAGUACUAUGGUACUUGAGGAAUUGGGAAUAAAAUGACCUGGAUCCAAACACAAACCCUCUUGCCCAACUAAGCUAAACACAGAAGAGUUGGUAUUUUAUUCUUGUUCCCUGCUCCUCUUAAAUAGCCAUGUCUAUUUCCAAAUGAAAAGUCUGCUAAUGACCUAGCAGGUUCCCAGUGUAGAUAGGAUCCAAUUAUCUGCUAUUUGGCACACAAUGGCCUUUCUGUCUGCCAGCCAUGUACCAGGGGGUGAAAAUAGCAUGUCUACUUUAUUCCUGAGCGUCAGGGUGUUUUUCUACUAGAAAAAAAAAAUAAAACCCUGAAAAAUAGUUUUGAAACUCAGAGUAUUUUACUCAAAAGGUCAAAGAUUCAUUGGAAUUUAAUUUUCUUUUUCUUGUUAUUUUUAAGUUGUCAUUUUUCUGUAAUAUUAGUUGUGCUGUGUGUAUAUUUUCAGCCUGAGUUUUCUUUGUUCCUUACUACUAGAUUUUGCCUUAAACUCAUAAUCCUGACUGCUUUUCACAAUGUUCAUUUUCCCAUGGCAACAGAGAUGCAAAUGAAUAAUUCUGGUGUUACUGUGGGGAAGAAAAGAAGAACCUGUGUGUGACUCAUACAAGAAAAUCUGUUAUUCAAGAAUAAAUAUCGCAGCAGUAAUAAUAAAGGUUUCUUGAGUACAGGCGAUCAGGCUGCAAAGGGGAACUAUGGACUCCUUGAUCUCAUACAAGCUUUAAGAUGGACUAGUGAAAACAUUGGAUUCUUUGGUGGUGACCCCUUAAGAAUCACUGUUUUUGGAUCUGGUGCUGGGGGUUCAUGUGUCAACCUGCUGACUUUAUCCCAUUAUUCUGAAGGUAACCGUUGGAGCAAUUCAACCAAAGGACUUUUUCAACGAGCAAUAGCUCAAAGUGGAACAGCCCUUUCCAGCUGGGCUGUUAGUUUUCAACCUGCAAAAUAUGCUAGAAUGUUGGCCACAAAAGUUGGUUGCAAUGUUUCAGAUACAGUAGAGUUAGUGGAAUGCCUACAGAAGAAGCCUUACAAAGAACUUGUUGACCAAGAUAUUCAACCAGCUCGAUACCACAUAGCCUUUGGACCUGUGAUUGAUGGUGAUGUAAUACCAGACGACCCCCAGAUAUUGAUGGAGCAAGGAGAGUUUCUCAACUAUGAUAUAAUGUUAGGAGUGAACCAAGGGGAAGGGUUAAAAUUUGUUGAAAAUAUAGUAGAUAGCGAUGAUGGUAUAUCAGCUAGUGAUUUUGACUUUGCUGUUUCAAAUUUUGUUGAUAAUUUAUAUGGAUAUCCUGAAGGCAAAGAUGUUUUGAGAGAAACCAUUAAGUUCAUGUAUACUGACUGGGCUGACCGUCAUAACCCUGAAACCAGAAGAAAGACAUUACUGGCUUUGUUUACGGACCAUCAGUGGGUGGCACCAGCUGUAGCCACAGCGGAUCUUCACUCAAACUUUGGUUCACCUACGUACUUCUAUGCCUUUUACCAUCAUUGCCAAACAGAUCAGGUUCCAGCUUGGGCUGAUGCAGCCCACGGAGACGAGGUUCCCUAUGUACUGGGAAUCCCCAUGAUUGGCCCUACAGAGUUAUUUCCUUGCAAUUUCUCCAAAAAUGAUGUGAUGCUGAGUGCAGUUGUAAUGACAUACUGGACAAAUUUUGCUAAAACUGGUGACCCAAAUCAACCAGUCCCUCAAGACACGAAAUUCAUUCAUACCAAACCCAACCGUUUUGAAGAAGUAGCAUGGACCAGAUAUUCCCAGAAAGACCAACUUUAUCUCCAUAUUGGAUUAAAACCAAGAGUUAAAGAACAUUACAGAGCCAAUAAGGUGAACCUCUGGUUGGAGUUGGUACCUCAUCUGCAUAAUCUCAAUGACAUUUCUCAGUAUACCUCUACAACAACUAAAGUGCCAUCAACUGACAUCACUUUCAGACCUACGAGAAAAAAUUCUGUACCUGUCACGUCAGCCUUUCCCACUGCCAAGCAGGAUGAUCCCAAACAACAACCAAGUCCAUUUUCAGUGGAUCAAAGGGACUACUCAACAGAGCUGAGUGUCACUAUUGCAGUUGGAGCAUCACUGCUGUUUCUGAACAUCUUGGCCUUUGCAGCCCUGUACUACAAAAAGGAUAAGAGGAGACAUGAUGUUCACAGGAGAUGCAGCCCUCAGCGCACUACUACCAAUGAUCUAACCCAUGCACAAGAAGAGGAAAUCAUGUCCCUCCAAAUGAAGCACACUGAUUUGGAUCAUGAAUGUGAGUCCAUUCAUCCACAUGAGGUGGUUCUUCGGACCGCCUGUCCCCCAGAUUACACACUAGCUAUGAGGAGGUCACCUGAUGAUGUUCCCUUAAUGACACCCAACACCAUUACAAUGAUUCCCAACACUAUACCAGGGAUUCAGCCCUUACACACAUUCAAUACAUUUACUGGAGGACAGAACAAUACUCUGCCCCAUCCCCAUCCCCACCCCCAUUCACAUUCAACAACCAGGGUAUAGCCAGAUAAGAGAAACAAACUAUUUUUUUUGAUGGAUUGCAGUAAACGAUCACUGAAGAUUCCUUGGCUUUCAACCUACAAGACUUACUAUUUAAAUAAGGAGGAAUAUUAUGUGAAUAUACAUAUCAAGAACUUUGGGGGUUUUGAAAAAAAUGAAUUGUAUAUAUACAAAUCAACUUUAAAAACAAAUUUCAAUUGCUUGAAGCAAUUGUUCUGAAUGAUACUUUUUCAUUCACAUUCAAGAAUUAAUUUUUUGAAGAUUUAAGUUACAUAAUGGAAUUAGGCAUGUGGAACACCAAACAGGAAAGAACUAUGUCUGAAAUAUAAAAAAUAAAAAUAAAAAAACAACUAUGAAUAUGCACAAGGGACACACCAGUGGAAUGUCAGAUAAUUUUCACCAGUUUUUAUUUGGAGCCGUUUUAUUGUGUAGACCAUAUUUACAUAUUUGGAUAAGUACACAAAGCGUCAAUGCUGUUAAUGGCCUUAGCAAAGGCUCAUGCUGAAAUUUGCCAGUAAAACAAAGAAGUUUAAAGACUGGCAGGUACACCAUUAUCACAUAAGUGCUGUCAGUAUAAAGUUGUGGGGAUAAAGGAAACUGGAUAUUUUUAGCACGAUGUGCAUGAUAAUUUAUAUGCUUGGUGGCUGUGCUGCUGAUUAAGCCGUAAUUAAAAUUCUUCUCAUCCCAUUGGAGUUUUUAAUAGAAGCUUCCUCCAUCAAUUGGCAGAACCUAAAGAAGAUUUUAAGGGGCAAAAGUAAUUACAAUAAAAUAAUUCACAGUAGUUUCAAUAUAGAAGGAAUUAGCUAUUAAAGGUAUUUGAAGAAACUAUAGGUAUAGUGGUGAAUACUCGCUGAUAUGAAUCCCAGAAAAAAAUUUCCUGUUUUUAAUGUUCUUUUCAAUCCCAUCUAGAUAAUUUAUAGAAAUAUAACCCUAAUUGGACAUGUGGUACAGGAUCUAUAAGUUGCUGUGUUUUUUUGUUACUCUGUAUUUUGUUCCUUUUGGUAAGGUGAAGUGUGUCCAAAGAGUUACUUGCAACAGUCUUUCAUGAUAUGAGGAUGCCCCCGUAUUACCACUCUGAUUAUAGUUCUGAGUUCUUUGAUUUACUCAUGCUGCAUGACAAAAUGUUUACUAAUAACAAUUCAUUAUAAAGUUAUAUCCCUCUUUACAUCACUUAUCUUUCUCACUGAGGUUCAUUCACUGGAAUUUACUCACGCAAUCUCAGUAGAGUACAACGUAGAUACAGAACCUAGGAGAGUCAACAUCUGGAGGAUUUUAGUCUUUCUUACACAUAUGUGUGAUUUUAAACGAAUAUUCUCAGACCACAGGAAACUCUUCAUCCCCCUGUUGUUUACCAGUAACAGUAUAUCACAGACCUUUCCAAAUGUUUGUAUAUGUAAUCAGAUGUACAUUUAUAUUGAAAAACAAAUGAGAUGGACUUAAAGAGCACAUCCUGAUAAAUACUUUCUCUCUCACCUGUACUAUAUUUCUAUUAGACUAAAGUUAUGUGAUUUUUUUUUUACAUUUUUUCAGAUGACUAGCAAUUUUGAUAGUUUAUAAGAUAAUGCAAAGAACUUUCUCUGACAAACUAACUGCAGUAACAGAAACCUUUCUUUUCAGUUACUCUUUUUCAAGAAUGAAAGAUUAUUAUACAAAAAAUUGUAUACUACUUGAUGGAACCAACUUUGUACAUCUUGGCCAUGUCACUGGUCAUUGUGUGAAAUAAAGAUAAUCUGGAUAAUGACUAUUAGUCCAAUGCUAAGAAACAUGAUCUUUGCUCAUUAAAGAGCUAAAAUGUUUAUUGCUGUUUUGUCUUUCUUUUUUCUAAAAAAAGAAAAAAAAGAAAAAAAGGAAAAGAAGAACAAAGAAACAUGACUGUCUCAAAGAGUAAUUUUUCUAGAUUAGACCAGUCAGGUUUUUGAAGACAUAUAGGUAACUUCCACAGAAAACACAAACAUGUAUUUAAAGGCAAGUCUCAUCUAAGAUGAAACUCAUAAAAAUUAUUUAAUGUUUGUUAUGAAUUUAAAAGCUCCAGAAAUCCAUGAAAAAAAGAAAGAUUAGCUUUGUGUUGUUAAAUAUCUCUUAGGUACAGAUGUUGUAGAAAUAAAGUGCCAAUUGUUUUCAGUUAGUUAGAAAAACAAGUUCCAAUUCUAGUCAUCAAGGAAAAGGUCUAUUGAAAAGAAAUUUGCAAUAUUUCAUGGAAUACAAAUAACUAGGUUCAUAAAAUGGGGGUGAUUAAACUACCAUAAAGUAAUGAAUAGAAAGUUGCCAUGCUAAGAGAAUGUAAAAGUGCUGAGCAAGAUAUUAAACUGACACUAAAAGAUAAAAAUCUAUUUCAAGGAAUUUAUGUGAUUAUAAUCCCCCCUCCCAAUUAUUAUCUAUCAAAGAAAUGUAGGUAUUCCUCCAUAAUUAAAAAAAAGUCUCUGUUAGAAGCAAAAGUCUUCAAAAUCCAGAGUGAUCUACAUACAGCUUUUGACUGAGGUGGUUAUGCUUUUCAACUGUGAACUGCCAGUGUACACAAAUACAAAUAAUUGUUUAGCAUCUGAAGUAUUGUUCAAUUGGAACACUGUAUUUUACUGUAUUAAUUAAACAAAACACAAGAACAGAAUAGAAAUGACAACAAAAUAAGAUAUGAAUGAAUACUUUCAUAUGCAUUGCUUCAUUUGGCAAAACCAAACAUUCUAUUAAAUAGUAUGUUUUAACGAUGGCCAUAUUUAUAUCAUCUACCUACCAAUCUAUUGCUCUGCAUUUAUCAAUCUGCCUAUAUAUAGCAUAACUGUCACCCUCUUUAUAUUAAUUUAGGAAAAUGAUUGAGGAAAACAAAGCAUAGCCCUAUUAAUUAUUUUCUCUAAAUUAGGGUAGAAUAACUUUAUGGAAGAUAAAGCAGCCUAGGUUUAAUUGUUGUUCACCAGUCACGUGAUAAAGUCAUUGUGAAUGAGUGUUAGUUGCUAGUUUUAUAAUUGCAGUCUCUAGUUUCUGAAUGAAAAAGGAUGCCCCACAUUAUACAGAACAUUAAGAACUGUUUUUAAAGCUGAAACAUAAUCUUUAUAUGCAAGAAAAAUAAAUACUGUUACUCAAUUUUAGCAAAUAUGUUUAAAAUGUAUUUAUUUAGAUAAUUUUCUUUGAAAAACAAUGUAAGUAACAAAAUUAAAAUAAUAUUUUUGGCAUUAUUUGUUAAUUCAGAUUUUCCUGCCUCCGAUUAAAAAUUAGGCAAAGCUGCUUAUAAUUUAUACAAAGAUUACACUAAAAUGAACUUUAUUUCAUUGUUUUGCUGUUAUAUAAAAUUUUUACCAAAUGUUUACCAAGAGAUUAAUGUUUUAGAGUAUGAGGAUAGAAAAAUAAAAGUGACAGAUUUCAUAGUUUUAAAUCUCUACUGAACAUGUUGACUAUGAACAAAAUCUAAUUGGCUACCACAGAUAUAUAACAAAGUUUAUUACUAACUUUAUGCAAAUUGGAAAAUAAUUUGCUAAAGCAUUAAAAAUGUCAGAUUUGUAGACGUCUUGCUGGCAACUCAAAGCAGAAAAUCUGAGUAUAUAUUAUUUUAUUCCUCAUUUCAAAUAUAAAAGUUGACCAAAGUGAUGCUUUAUUUCCGACUUCCUGAUCUGUAUGUGAAAACAGCAACAUUUUUUUAAAAAUUAUCAAGUAUAUAUAAUAUUAAAAAGAGGAAAACAGAUGGCACUAAUUUUCUUACAGGAGUGAAGUGCUGAAACUAAAUUGUUACAUCUGUAACAACAGUUAUUUCACCUCUUGCCACACUCAUCCUGACAUACGUAUUAAUAUCAAAAAAUGAUACAAAGAAUAUGAGAAAUGUGUUCCAGCAUUAAAGACACUACUACAUAGAAAUUACUGGGAUUCUUUUCUUUGGCGAGUUUCACUGAAAUAGUUUCACAGGAUGAAAUGAUGAAUUGAAUUCUUAAGAAGCUGUCAAAUAUGGCAGUCUUUUGAUGUUAGUAAUUUUGUUUUCUUCUGUGUUAUUGGUUCAAAGUACUGGCCUUUUCCUUCAUUUCCAGUAAUUAGUUGUUAUAGACUAUCACUUUUUAAUGUGAGUGGAAAUUAGAUGAUUUGGUUAUACUUGUGAAAACAUGCUUCCAAAUAAAUUCAAUUAAUGGGCACUUCCCUGCUGAGAUUUUGUUAUCAUUCAUUUGAUUAUCUUGUCAAGCUUUACUGUUACGACAAAUGUUUUAGCUUUCUGGUCAAUAGACUAAGGGAAUUUCUCCAGUAGCCUUAUACCUCUCCUGCACUUGAUCUGAUAGCAACAUACACUUCAAAUUUCCAUCAGAAGUCUCUAAAGAAAUUUCCUACUGCUAUGAAACAUUUGGUGGCCAACUUGAUUCUUUUUCAUAAGCAUUCUGAUUUGAUUUUAUUCUGGCACGUUGCUGUAUUUGGAUGCAGGCCAGAAAUCAAUUCCAUUUGAUAAGGGUUGUGGAGAAUACAGACUGGAAUAACCGUGUGCAGGGCUUAAGUGCCUUUUCCUCCUGAGAUUUUAUUUAUAAAACUUAGCUUUUUUAAAUUUUCAGAUUCAGAUAAUUCAAUUUAAAGAGUACAAUAGGAUGACUAUAUUAUAAAUUACCAAUAAAGAAAGUUUAUUUGGACAUUUUUACAUUUAAUUUGAUUUUUAAAAUAAUAUCAGAUGCAUCUAAAUGGCUUCCGGGAAAGACUGAGGUAAAUUUUUGAAAGUGACAAUUAUAUAGGCAUCUGACUUGAUGGUACUUAAGAAUAAAAAUUUAAAUCUCUAGCAAACUUUAAAAAUUGUCCAAAUAGUAAGUUUAAUUUGAAAGAAGUCUGAAGCUAUUAGAGAAAAUCAUGUACUAGAUAGGUAUAUAUUUUUUUCUAGUCAGCUAUUACGUACACCACAUAAUAUAUAUACCCUAUAUACUAUAUGGUUUAUAUAACAUUUAUAAUGGCCCUUUCAGACCCAUAUACUUACAAAUGACAUUGUAUAACUACCUACAUAUGUAUUAAUGUGACAGAAUUUAGUCCUUUAUGGAAAGUCAAACCAAAUUGCUAGCAGUUUUGAGUUGAAAUGAAUGAUAACAAUUAAAGCUUUUAAGAAAUUGGUAAAGGUACCGUAACAAAAACUCAGCAGAUAAAUUUAAAAGAGAGGGACCAUUUUUGAAUGCCAUUUUCAGAGUUGACAUCUAAACUAGAUGGUGUGUUUAAAAGGAUUUUAGUGGUUUUGAUUCAUCCUUUCUCUGCAUUCAUAUCAUUUAGCAAAUUAAUGGGACAUAUGUCAUGGUUUUUGUAAAAAAGACCAUUGGGUUGUCAUGAUUCAGUUUGUGUUUGGACAUCUAUGGCUUUCAUUAAAAACGUGUUUAUUAUCAUGAAUAAAUAUUACCAUGUUUUCCAAGUUGUGUUGACUAUUUUUAAACUCAGAAAUAAUUUCUUCUCUAUUUGUCUCACACAAAAAGGUUACUAAGAUAAGUGUUUUCUUACAAAGUCUUUGUAUUGCUUCCACACUGCUGACAGUUCUGACUUGAUAGAAACAAUGACAUUUUAUGAUCUUUUCACCUCUUGGUGAAUGCAGGGCAAGAAUUUAGAGAAUAGAUUUGGGGAGCUGGACACAACUUUUCAGAAAAGAGAGAGGAAAGUGGGAGAAGGAAAAAGAAAAGAAUGGAAAAAGGAGGAAGUGAGAGAGAACAAAAAGGAAGAAAAACUUCUCAAUUUUAAAUUAAUGACUUUUUGCAUCCAAAUAGUGCUUUAAAUAGAGAUGUGUGACAGUUUUUUAAAAAGAAGGGCAAAGGAAUUUAAAUAAAUCCCUUUAAAUCAUAAAUCUAUUAUUCUUAGAGAACAAAAUUAAUAAUAUCUAGGAAGAUAUCUUAAAUUUAAUUCUUGAUCCAAGUCUUGAUCAAAUCAUGUCACUGGAAACAAUUAAAAAUAAAAUCUAUACUGAAAUAUUUAUGGUUUUGUACUAUCUAAUCAAUAAUGAUAUUGGUAGGAAGACUAUGGGAAGUAAGAUAAUCUCUCAUCUGUAUAUAGCCCAAGAUAAGAAUACAGCAAAGAGGACAUCAUAUAAUUUCCUCAUACAUAGCCUAAAGAUAAAUGUUUCCAAUGGCUGAAUAAAAGAAUUAGCAUUGCUUUACAAGUCUCUGUGGUCACAUAUGGCCAUGGGCACCUAAUAAAUUAAACAGUUAAAAAACAUAUUCUAACAAUUUCACUUUCCAUAAAAGGGUUUUGAUGUUUUGUAAAAUUUGGUGUUGUUUGAUAUGAUUACUUUUUCACUAGUUUUGUAUUUCCUUAUGGUUUGUAGGAUGUUAUUUCUGAGUUCAAAAAAAGUUUCAAAUAUACUCGUGAAUGUUCAUGUGAAAGCAGUAUUUUCUAAUGGAAUGCUAUAAUUUGAAGUACUGUCUCAAUUUUGGAGAGUUGAUUGACUAUCUAGUUAAAACUUUUCUAUCUCCCCUGAAAAUACUCAACUUUGCUCUCAGAGCUGCCUUCCUCUGCACUACAGGGGAUCUUCUUACCAGUCACUGUGGCUCCUGUUUCCAUGGCCUAUCCUAUUACUAGUUAUGACCUCUUCUCCAAGGGGGUAAAGUUGUGCUGAAAGUCUUAAAAGGUGAUCUAACCAACUGGUGCCUUGGGAAUUGGCUUCCUCUGCUCCUCAGGCAGGUUAGAAGCUAGUGAACAUCAAUCAAGCAAUGAAAGAAAUUAGUCAUUUCUUCUUUCAACAAAUGUUGUCUACUAUGGGUUAGGCAACAUAAUGGGUGUUAAACACGUGGCCAAUUCUAUGACUUACUAACAUACAACUAUUGUCAAGUUUGGAAUAGGUCCAAACACAUGGACUGAUUUAGACCACUUUCUAUGCUAUACUCUGUAGCAAAUCACUGUACAAUUCCUUGUUUUGUCUAUUUCACAUGUCUCAAAAUAGUAAAUACAAAUCAAUAUUUCUUGAGUUCAAAAAAAAUUAGUGAAUUCUAUUGAGCCAGUUCACCAGUUAAGGUAUGUAGCAGACAUCUUUCCAAAUAAUAAAUACAGCCUAUCUGAAGUCAUGCUAUAGUAUGCCAAUUCAAAUUUCAUGGAAUAUGAAAUUUCCAGCAUAAAUCUCAUCUGAUCCAGCCCCAUAAGUGGUUCCUUAAUCCUUUGCCACAACCUCAACAUGUAAUUGUGAAGCCUAUCAUUGAACACUGCCAUGGGUCUGAAUUCUAAAACAGCUGGCUGCAUUUUGGACUAUUUGGGAUGUCUUCUUUAUAUUGAUUUCUUGCUCUUUUUUUUUCUUUUUAUAGCCACACCGUCUUCAUCGCCUGAAUUGAUCUCAAAUAUUUAAAGAUGGCUUUCAUAUCUUCCAUGAGUUAUUUUCUCCUGAAAGCAAAAAAUCCCACUUGAAAUACAAAAUAGUUCAGUCUUUUCACAAUUCUAAUCACUGUUCUCCAAAUUUGCUCCCAAGCCUAAGUUUCUUAGAAAGUUUAAUGUCUAGGAUUGACCAUAAUAAACACUUACGUAUAGUUCAUCUCUGCCUAACAGAGCUCCACUAUCAACUUCCUCAUUACACAAAGUAUAUUUAUUUUAAUAUAACUUGCAAUACUAUUACAUUCUUUGUUGGCCAUAGCAUACUAGUAAUUCAGAUUGAGAUGUACUUUCUACUAAAACUUUAAAAAUUCUAAAUGCACUAUUGUUAAGCAAAUUCUGUCUUUCUACUGCCCUUGAUCAUUUGAGUUUUAUUGUAUGUUCAGGAUAUUAAAUACUAUUAAAUUCUACCUCAUUAGGUACAGCACUACAGCCUAUGGAGACCUAUCUAUCCACCUCAGAGUAAGGAAAUCAACAAAGAUGAUAAACUUCUAUCUUCAUCCAAGUCACUAACAAAAACUACCAUGCAGAAUCAGGUUGAGGAUAAAUCUCCAGAAUAAUAGUAAUAGAGACAGUGUGUAAAGUACUGACAAAAGCAAAAGAUGACAAUUACUAAGCCCUUUUAUGUUCCAGAUUCUGUAUCACACUCCACAACAAACUCCCACAUACCACCCUCGAAAUAUCUACUAAUACUUGUUGAUGUGCUUAUUCACUAAUUCGUUGUUUAAAAGAUUAUUAUUAAGCAUCUAUUAUAUAUGAGUUACUGAGCUACUUGUUAAUGAUAGAAAAGUGAAUAAAAUGUGGCUCCGUUUCUCACAUUACUAGCAGCCAACUGAUUACUCUUCCUCUUUUCUACACACACAGCACAAAAGACACAAUCAGAUGUAUUUGCAGGAUAUAUUUUUUUCCCAUGUAAAACAUUUGCCUGACAUCAUAGUCAUCUUUAGUAAGAAAACUGGGAUAAUUACUCUAAACUUUCUAUUUGGGAAUUUCUGGGUUCCUGGUGCAUUAUAUUAAAUGUUAGAAGAUAUAGAAAAAUAAUUCUCACACCAAUCACCUGUCAUAAUUAAGAUGUGAAUUUAGGCCAGUCAAGUGUUGUCUUAAAGUGGGAUUCCUUGUAUGAAAAAGUAAUACAUACAUAAGAUAAAACAAAAUAUUUUAAAGUGAAAAGUAAACAUCUCUCUUACUACAGAUUCUAAUCCCUUAGUCUUUUUCCCCAGAGACAUUGACUCUCACCAAUUUGCAUAUAAAUCUCUACAAAUAUGUCAUUCAUGUGUAAACAUGUAAAAGUGUAUUGUCUGUGUAUGUACGUGGGGGCACUUUAUAUAUAUAUAUGUAUGUAUAUAUAUGUGUAUAUAUAUAUGUAUGUAUAUAUAUGUGUAUAUAUAUAUAUGUAUAUAUAUAUAUAUACAUAUAUAUUCUUUUUUUAAAUUUAUCUGGAAAUGUUCCAUGUGAGGAUACUACAUGUCAGCUCUGAGGAGAAAAUAGAAGAUAAAAGUAAGUUUCAAAUUUCUCCUUAAAUUCACGGCUAUUCCAAUCAAAAUUUCAACACUGUUUGUUUGUUUACAGACUUUAGGUGAGUAAGGGUCAGGAAUAGCCAAGAUUAUUUUGAAUCAAAAGAAUCAGCAGCAAAGACUUUGUCUACCGUAUUUCAUGAGUUACUAUAAAGCUAUUGUAAUCAAAACAGUGUUAUAUCAAUUCAGAGACAGACCAGUGUAGGAUAACAUUGAACCCAUAAACAGAUCUAUGAAGAAAGGGGAACAUGGCAUAUAAAUGGAAAUACAAAUCAAGAGAAAAGAGAGAUGCCUCAGCUAACAAUAUCCCUAUGUCAUACUAGACACAAAAAUCAAUCCCAGACAAAUUAAAAAUAUAAACAUAAAAGCACAUUUUAAAUGUCUCAGAAUACAUAGGAAAACAUUGUCAUGUCCUCGAAAUAGGGAAGAAUUUAUUAACAAGACAUAAAACAGCAUAAACAAUAAAGAAAACGAAUAACAAGUUAAAAUUAAAAUGUUAAUACAUCAGAUAAUGAGUUUUUUUAAAUGACUAUAAGCACAUAUUGAAAGUAAGUAUUUGCAACACAUAUAAGCAAUGAAAGAUUAAUUAAUAUGAGUGGAUAGAAAAUUCCUGUAGUUUAAAUAAGGAAAGGACAAAUUCACAAGGAAAAUAGAGCUGAUUAAAUACUGGGAAUAAAGGACAUGUCUGUUUUUUCCCUGUUGCUGAUUCUCACAAAAAUGUAAGGAGAGGACUGAAAAAUAUAUAAACUUAUCAGAACAAAAAGAAUAGAAAAAGAGAUAACAGGUAAGAAGUUCUGACAAGUUUUUGAGAGAGAGAAAUUAGAUAAACUAAAAAACCUUAAGAAUAUAAUACAACCUAUGAAAUAGCAACAUAAAUCAGAAUUAGAAAAGUUAAAAGAUGCUUUAAUAAAACUCAAGAAAGAAUUAUAAAUAAAAGAAAAAAUAAUUUUUUAAAUUAAGACUAAAUUAAAGGAAAUGCAGACCAAAGAAUGCUUUAAGAGACAUAGAAAAAUUUUCAAAAAGAAAUGGGAAUAAAUAGUAAAAAGUAGAAAAAAUCUAAAAAGUUUCAAAAAAGAAGGAAUAGGGGAUGUGAGCUGAGGGGGAGAGGAAGGGAGAAAUAAGAAAAAAAAUCAAGCAUAAGUGAUAAGAAGAUAGAAAAAGAAGACUCAAUAUGCAUGUAUAUGGAACCUUCGAAAAAGAAAACCAAAACAAGGAAACACAACAAAUACAAUGAAAGCUGUAAUUCAGGAAAUCUUUUACAAUACAACAGAAAAAAAUUUGAUGUCACAUUUUCAAAAGGCACACUGAAUAUAUGAAAUAACUGAUCAAAAAUGACCAACAUCAAGACAUAUGCUAAUAAGUUUAAUGACUAUCAAAGAAAUAAUAUAAGCAUUCACAUCUAGCUAAAAUCACCAAAUCUCUUAAAAUGAAGACUCUUUUGUUAUAUAAUUAGAUCAUCAUCAGACUUCAAAGACAACGCUUUAUGCCAGUAAAAAUUAAAGUAACAUACAAAAGAUAAGACGUUAGAAUGUAAGCAAGUUAUUUUUAUAUUCAGCCAUAAGCUAACUUUCCUACAAGUAUGAAGGGCAUGGACAAACUGUUAUUGGCAUUAAAGAACUCAGGGAAUAUUGUUACCAUGAACGCCUCCUGAGAAAUUUACCAGAAAAAGACCUGUAGACAAACAGAAGGGUGACAUGGAUAUAAGGACUGAUAAUGGGCACUAAAUACCAGAGAGCUAACACUAAAUGAGGGCUAUAUGGUGGAGUACAGUAUAAACUUGUUACAUGUUCUGAUAAUGAAGACACGGUACAGCUAUAAGAAAUAUGAAGGUAAUAGAAAAAUCAUAGGUAAAAAUUGUCAUUACUUUCAAUAAUCAUAUUUACAGUGGUAGCAGUGCUGUUGCUACUCUGAAACUGCUUUAUGUGUAACACAGAAUACAGCAAAGAGGGAUAUUGUGAUAUGCUAAUUGUAUCAUCUCCACCGUCUUUGAGAACCAGCACUCUUAAUGUGGAAGAAAGGAUAUUCUGAAUCAGAGUAGAAGAGGUUAAGUAAAAACCCACCUUAUUGUUUCGAUUUUAAAGUGUAACUAUCAGAAUGAACACUUUAAAAAAAGUUAUGCAAACUAUGAUCAAGCUAGUAGCAAUGAGCAUCCUUAAGGACCAGAUUGUGGUUUUAAAAGAACAUUUCUUACUGUAAAAAAUUCACCACGCACACAAACACACAUAGAAAUAGAGGUCUGGGGAACAAACCAUAGAAGGUGAACCUGGAACAUUUUGUCAAAGACUUCUAGGAAUAUAUCUAAAGGACAGAGGAACCAAUACAAAGAUGAUCUCACUAUCUAAAGAUACGACAGUGUGAGCAUCAAUAAGGAUAAUUUCAAUUAAUUGAAAAUAAAUCCAAUUUAAAUUCUAAAGUGAAUAAUAAUUAAAAAGAAAACAUCUACCACUUAUGGCAGAUAAUUGGAAUAUAAUUCAUUGUUUUGAAAAUUCAUAAGUAAAAAGAACAGUUAAAUAUUUUGUCCUGCCAUUCCUCCACCAACUAUACAGCAAGGUAGCCAAAUGGUAGAUGAGAAUUUACUCUUUGUAGAAGUUAUUUCAGCUAAUAAAAGAAGGAAUUGUUGUAUUAUAAUUUCAGUUGUCACUUGUUUUAUUGCUCCCAAUGAAUCAGUGGAUCUAGGUAUUAAGCAUCACAAAAUUAGAAAUAAUGAGUUAUCAUGUGUCUCCUGGAUAGAUGUACACAAGAUUACCUCAGAAAAGGCUUGCACCCAAAACCAAACCUGUGUAUGAUGGAAGUCUCUAGGUUCAACUGUCAGAAAAUACAUAGGUACAGGAAGUACAUCAAAGAAGCAUGUUAAAUUAUACCAUGGAUAUGAAAUCAGAAAAAUUCACACGAUUUAAAAUUUUCCCAGUUUAAUUUUCUUGUAUCCUCAAUAAAUAAAUUGCAAGAAAAAAAACACAGUGAGAAAAUAUGUAGAUUUUUAAAAACUUACAAAUACUUUUUAAAAAAGUUCUGCUUCAGGAAGAACGAUUCAGUAAUAAAAUUAUAAAGGACAGCAAGAUGGGGUAACCUAAAAUAGUGUUGAUAGAUCACAGAGGAAAUAAGCUGUGACUGAGAUGGUGCAUGUGGAGGUUUUUUUUGCAGUGGCUUGCAAAGUGCUAUCUCUUAAUCUGGGUGUUUUUUACCUGAGCCUUUUCCUUAUGAUGAUGUUUUAAACCAAACAUUUACUUCAUGAUGUUUUUCUGUACCUGGAUUAUAUUUUACAAUAAAAUAAAUAGGAUUGUAAUAAAAUUAAUAAUACACGACAAUGUUGCAGACUUAAAGAACAUGAGUUUAUUAAUUGAAAGGACCCGCCAACUGCCCAGUGUAAUGGAUGAAAAAAACACCUGUGAAAGCAUACCAUCACAAAAUGUCAUGACUUCAGAAAAAAGAAGAAAAGUUUCAAAGCUUCCUCAGAGGAACAAAAGGAAUUCUCAACGUCAGCUCUGGAAGCUAGAAGAAAUUGGAUAAUAUUUUUGAGAAAGAAUUAUGAUCAACCUAUAGAAUUUUAUAUUCAAACAAAAUAUAAGUUCACUGUAUCAGUCCACAAAGGCAUAGAUUCAGGGGUGAGAGGAAAUAAAAAACCAGGAUUGCUGCUCAGGAGACUAGAGAACAGCUCAGAGUGUGAAGCUGGGGAGUUGUAGAAAGAAUAUCUAUACAAUAAAAUUAAAACUGACGUAUUUCAUCAUGUGGAAAAAAGUGUUAUUUGUAUAGAUUUUACAAUUUUUUUUGCUAAAUUUGGAAAGAACAUAGAAAACUACACAACAAAAUCAAAACUAUUAAUGCAGAGAAAAAGAGAAAGUACUACAAGAAAUGGAAUGUAAUCUUUGGAUAUAUAUUUGUGCACAUGAAUGUAAGUACAGAUAAUUCUUCCAAAUAGAAAGUUUGGAAAAAGCAUAUUUUAAGGUUUUUAUCUACCAAUUUACUAAUUGAUUUAAAAAGAUGUUAUUCAAAUUUACAUUCCACAAACAGUGUAUUAAAGUAUCUAUUUCCCUACCCUCUAACCAAAAAUCAGUGUAUCAAUUUUUUAUAUUUUCCAUUUCAAUAUAAAUGUAAUAUCAUUAUUGUAUUAAUUUGCAUGUUUAAAUUGAGGUAAAACAUCUUUUCUUAUGCUUAUAAGCCAUUGUAUUUCUUUUUAUAUUAGAUGUAUUCCUUUACUUUGUAUAUUUUUUCUAUUCGUUUAUUAAUCUCUUCUUAUGAAAUUAUAAGAGUUCUCUAUAGACAAAUAAAAUCAGUACUUUUGGUCA